GUUUUCUAAGAGUUGGAGAGGGAAGGGAAGGAGGCAGUGGAUGGCCAGUGUGCCUGAAAACUGGAAUUAGAUCGGUGAACUGAGAGGAUUGGUUUCUGCCCUACGUUGGGUGAAGAGGGGCAGUCCUCAUUGCUAACAGCCGCAGGUUGGUGUAAUUAACUAACUUCCGUAGGCAAUGCCCGGUGUACAUCUUGAAAACCCAUCAGAUGGGGUAUUUCUCACUGACAUCAGCUUUUAAAGGGAGGAGGGCUCAUAGUUGUAUCACAGCUGCAGUACUUUUCUUUAAGGCAAGAAACAGUUUAAAUCAGAGAAAAUUUCACAGGAUUCUAGAUCGACUACUUUUUUCAUCUAGUUCUAUUAUUUUGACCUUAUGGCCGUUUUUUGUUUGUUUAAUGGCGUGAAUUAAAGUGUGACAUUUCUGUCCAUCUUUUCACGUACAAAAUCAGCAUUCGUUAAUUCAGGUUAUGAAAAUAAUUGCUGCUUCAACAAAGUGAGGCUUAAAAUACCACAACAGAAAUGUAGCCGAUAGUAUGUAUCUUAACUUUUAGUUUAUAAUGACUGUAUUAAAAUGAUAUUACAGUUUUAAGUUUUUCAAACAAAUAGUGAAUGGUUGUGCAAAAUAAGACACUGAAAUAUUUUUUAAAGAAUUAAAAUCACAAAUGUUGAAUGAGAAAAAUAGUUUCUGAGAAUUUCUUUGCUAAAUCAGGGCAAUUUGGUUUAUUGCCAAACUGAUUAAGGAGGGGCUGAUUUCAUAAGCUAUAAUAUCUGUACUUUUAUGUCAUCUCUGAUAUAACAGUAUAUAAUGUAUUUAAGACUGCAGAUCAUCAUUAAACCACAUAAUGAUUGUUACACAGAUAAAAUAAGAAGCUUAAUUUGUAGCUAAAGACUGUAUCUUAUUGAUUGUAUAGUUGAUGUUGUGUUGUGCAGGAGGUAAGAAAUAUCCUAAGUAAGAAACAGAAUAUUUUAAAAAAAUAUUUACAAAAUCAUAUAGUUGAGUCAAUAUCUAUAAGUGAGGCUUAAUCCAUGCAAAUAAAUUGUUUUAACAAGGGCCUGUGGCUUUAAGAAUGACACUUGAUCUAUAUGCUGUAGAAGGCUUGUAGAAGUUGUCCUCAUAUUAGUUUAUACUAUGCACACAAUAUGUCCUUAUCUAGCCUGAUGCAUGCUCUAAAACAGGAAGCAUAAAACCAAGACGACACCAGGUAUGAAUAAAUAGUAAGAGUUAGGAGCUGGAGCUGACUCCACUGUGAAUUCUCCCACUCACUUGUUCACAGGUUUCUUCCUGCAGGCUUCAGGAUGAACAAUCCUGGCUGAAAUGUUCACAGGAAACCUUUUUGUUUUGUUUUUUUUUAAUGAAUAUUUUUUAGGUACUUGCUAUUUGAAGAAACAAAGUCAAGGUGAUUUAAGGGCCAGGCAAAUAUCCCUUAAAGACCUUUGUUAUAAUAUAGCCCUUUUAUUAUAUUUGAAUAUAUGCUCAGAUGCCUGCAGAAUUUCAUGUUCCAGUCAGGGUAGAGCAGGCUAAUUUUUAAGGGACAUGUGCUUCAGUACACAAAUAGGGUAAUAAAUAAGACUAACAAGUGUGCAUUCAGGCUACAUGUAUAAGAGGGUAAGAGGUGAGACAGCCACACCAUAUGAGGAUAGGGUUGGGUGGAAACAAAGCCAGGCUAAUGGAAAGCCUUGCCUGCUCUCUUCUAGAAAAAAAUUGAACUCAGGUCAGUAAAUAGUGCUGCACUCUGGGAGAGACAAGUAUAUGACAGGUCUUUGCUUUAUGUGAAGCUUACAGUGGGACUAGGCUUACCCUGGCAAAAUUAUUACAGAACAAGAAAGACUUUGCAGUAAAGAGCAACAGAAAGAAGAAAUGCAGAGCUACAAAUACUUUCUUUAGCAGAUAUACGUAUACAUUGUAGGGAAAACGUAAAAGAUCAGCCUUCGUGCCCUACAGACCACAGUUAAUAGUGAUGUUUGUGGCAGUUUUUCCUUAUUGCAGAUUAUAAAUAGUUCCAGGGAACAAAUAAUUACUAAUGAUCAACUUAUAGUUGGAGAUAUUAUAUUGCAUUGGUCUCUCACAAUGGAGGUUCUGCUUUGACACUAUCCAAGAGUGGCAUUUGGGUGAAUAAAAAGAGAGGGGAAUAGAAAAGCUACAACUGAAGCAUUAGUUAGAACACUGUCAAUGCCAAAUCACAACUGCUUUGUGCUGUGGAUUCCUUUCUGCAGGCUGCAGGAUGAAUGAUCCGGGUUGAAACACACACAGUACACUGCAGAACUGAGACUGUGACCCAUGGGCUUUCUCCUGCUGGCCCCUCUCAGAUAUUCCAGUUGGUGUUGCUAGCUUUACAGUCUCCAUGGGCCUAUUUACCUUGGUAAUUUGCACCUGAUGCAUUUAUAUUGGUAAUUUUUUUUCUCCCUGGAACCCUGGGAUCUCAUUUAUUCACUAGUGCAAUGAAGUGGUGGAGUGAAAAUCCCUCCCUAACUCAAGGAGGGGAAGAAUUGUUUAGGGAAAAUAGCAACCCUGCUAACUGCAGCUCUAAUUAAAACACCAAAAGAAGACUUGUUCUUAUUUAGACGUUGGCUAAUACCUGUAUCUCUGUGCACAUAUAGGCCAAUGCUAGUCCAUCUGUGGGCAUCACUGCUAACUUGCUAACCCUUUAAAAAAAUCCAGUGUCAAUAUGUUUUUGUUUCAAAAGAAAACAAUGACAGCCCUAGGAUGGAAACACAGGAAUUCUUUGGCCACAGCUUGCUAAAACCAUGCUUGGUAGUAUGUGCAUGUAGGGAAAAUUACUUUGAAUAACAAAAGCACAAACAAGGACUCAUAGAAUAAUAAGCAAUUAAGGUGGAUUAACAACAGUUGCCGAAUUCCAGCUGUUGGCUGCAGAUGCAGGCUCUUUAAUUCAAACUAGUUGCAACCUGUUGUUACUCAGAGACAGAAAGGGAGAAGAGUAUAUCCCUGGCAGUGCCCAUAUCAGGGCAGGUUUAUUGUUGUGCAUUGUGGGAGAUUUAAGUAUUGAGGGUAUGUUUACUUUCUCCCGAUUUAAAAAAAAAUUUCAUCUUUCUUCUCUUUUUUUGACAUCUUCCUAUAUAUAUUUGUGUCUUUCGAUUUAGAAUGACUAACCAAAAUCUAUGUGCUUGCUAUUUGGUUAUGAUAAUGAAAAAGGAGAAGAGAGCAAAGCAGGUGUCUGUUUCCAAUGGAAAUCUCACAGUAAAAGAAAUCAAAGACUCCUUUGGCUGAUACACAUACAUACAUACAUACAUACAUACAUACAUACAUACUUAUAUACAUAAAGAAAAGCACAGGCCCCAACGACACAACCUGGGGAAACUAUAUGAACAGGUAAUUUACAGGGUAAUCACCAUAUGUAGUCUAUCCCCUGCAGCCUUAUCACAGUGUGUACAUUGGCAUCAAACCUACCUCCUUGGAAAGCCUCAUUAUUAGUAUUCAGGAAUAGUCCCUCUAAGCAUAUUGGCCAGAGGUCUGAGGUGCAGGGCUAGCUUCAUGGCAUUCAACCUGUGCUGUCACACAGGGCCCUGAGCUCAGAAGGGCCCCAUACUUGGCUUAAGGCUCCGCUGUCACUGUCUCAAAAUUCUGAAUUUUAUCUUUGAACUAGUGUUUCAUAAAUGGAGCAUCUUCAUGAGCCGAGGCGAUGUGUGAUAUGUUUGUUUGUCCAUUGUGGCACUAUCUGCAUAUCACAUUCACAGUUUUUCACAAAUACAGAAUUCUGAUAGACUAUGAUGUGUGGGGGUCCAGGGAAGCUCCAGGGGAGUAGAAAGUAAGUGGAUUAUGGAAGCUGUCUGUUCCUGUAGUGUGUUGGUAUAAUAUGCAUGAAUCAAGAAAUUUGUGAGUGAGUUUCAGUUGAGUUAGUUGUGUAGUGUUUCCACUGCCCUAGUAAGAAUGAAAUAAAUAUACGUGUAUGAGCUAUGAAAAAAGGUUGUGUCAUAUUAUUCCACAUGUAAGUUAAAUGCUCUUAUAUUUGCAUUGAAACUGUCACUGUACCAUAUAAAGAUAAAUUGUAGGCCGGGCUUGUUGGCUCACGCCUGUAAUCCCAGCACUUUGGGAGGCCGAGAAAGGCGGAUCACUUGAGGUCAGGAGCUCAAGGCCAGCCUGGCCAACAUGGUGAAACCCCGUCUCUACUAAAAAUACAAAAAUUAGCUGGGCAUGAUGGCACAUGUCUGUAAUCCCAGCUACUUGGGAGGCUGAGGCAGAAGAAUCACUUGAACUCAGGAGGCCGAGGCUGCAGUAAGCCGAGAUCGCGCCACUGCACUCCAGCCUGGGUGACAGAUUGAGACUCCGUCUCAAAAAAUAAUACUACUAAUAAUAAAAAUAAAGAUAAAUGGUAAACUUCAUGCUAAUAAUUAAAUGUUUUAGUUUUUCUCUCCUUUGUUCAGAAUGACUUUAAAUAGCAAAUAAAAAACAUCAUGAGAAAUUGAAAGUUUGUGGAAGAAAGGAAAAAGCUUUAGAUGUUAGUGUUCUUAAUGGCACUGUUUUUUUCUUGCUUUUUGAACAAGGAGUCCUACAUUCUCAUUUUGCACUGUGCCCUGCGUGUUAUGUAAUGGUCCCCACAGAGGUGGUCUAUAGCCUCAGAUUUAAGUGGAACAAACUGAAGAAGUUGCUAAGAUUUUCCAGCGCUCCCUAGGUAGCCGUGAGAUGCAGACACCAAACAAGCAUCUUAUGCCUUCUUUAGAACUUUAGCUGAUGCAAACCAGACAGGUUCCCAUUUAAUCAGAUCUCACCACAUUUCAAAGUUUCUAUCUAUUCAAAAAAUCUUUCCCAGCCUUUACGUCUUAGGCAGCCUAUCUUUACAUGACUAUUAUUUCUCCAGUAUUAUUUCUCCAUAUAAGGCUCCGUUUACCUUCUAGAUGUGGUUAGCAAAAGGAGUAAUUUUAUACCAAUACAGUUACAUAAAAUAGCCUCCCUGCCCAGGCCUCUGCCUCUGAUCCUCUCCUGAUUUUUUGUUUUCAGCAGAAUAUGAACCUGUUCCUACAAAUGAGUUAGGAGAUGUAAAUGUGUUGAUUUAUUUGUCCUCAUGUACAUCAACAAUUUUUUAUAAAAGAUCACCUACUACUACAGAUAGCAAAGCAAAGCCGACUAAUGCUUUGCUCGCGAUACCAUGGCAACUUACUAACCAGCUUCUAGGCCCAAAUUGUCUUAAUAAAUGGAAGCAACCUCAGGGAGCUGGUUCUGAAACUACAGGUGCCUACUUUGGGACAAUGAGAAUGCUUGUCAGGAGGAGGGCAGGUGGUGAGCCAUGCCAAAGGAGUCCAGGGGACAUUGUCCCCAUUAGCAUAAAGCCAAGACUCUAAAUGGAUAUGACUUGCUCCUAGGAGCCAAACACAUGAACUGUCUACUUGGUACUUUCUGAAAACUACUUUGUCUCAUUCAGGGAGAUUAUGGCCUAGUCUGAAGGAGGAGAAGCCAAAAGCCCUGCUACAUCUGGGUUUAGUCCUAGGUUUGCUGACCCACGUUUCUUCUCCAGGAUGUUCCUCCCCAGGAAUGGGUCAUCCACUAAUGGAAGUUGCAGUUAUUGUUUAAGCGCACUUUAUUGCUUAGCAAGCCCCAACAGACAGCACCAGCUGUUGUCUGGGGUAGAGUUGGCAACAUUUUCCCACAAAAGGCAUCUUUGUAUAUUCUGCUACAAAUCUGUGUCAGUGAGAGCAGGAAGGAGGAGAGGGGUAAGACCUACCAAACAUGUAGGUAGCGUUGUGAUAAGGUACUUCUCAAUCCCUCCUAAAGGCCAAAUGCUCAUCCUCUAUGGAAACACAAGCAGCUGAACUGGAAUAACUUGACAUUACCUCUCAGAAACAUGGGAUGAACGAGACUCUCUGAUCUUGUCUGUAGCAAAGAGAUGCUGGGUAGUUGUUGUUUUUUGUUUUUUUGUUUUUUUUUUUUUUUUUGAGAUGGAAUUUUGCUCUCGUUGCCCAGGCUGGAAUACAAUGGUAUGAUCUUGGCUCACUGCAACCUCUGCCUCCCAGGUUCAAAUGAUUCUGUUUUCCGAGUAGCUGGGAUUACAGGUGCCUGCCACCACGCCCAGCUAAUUUAUGUAUUUUUUUUUUUUUUUUUUUUUUUAGCAGAGACAGGGGUUUCACCAUGUUGGCCAAGCUGGUCUCGAACUCCUGACCUCAGGUGAUCCACCCACCUUGGCCUCCCAAAGUGCUGGGAUUACAGGCAUGAGCCACCGCGCCAGCCUGCUCUAAGUAAUUUUGGGGAAAUUGGGUUGACGUUAGAGGAAGGACAGAAAAAAGAGGCCUGGACAAGCAGUCAGGAGGUGGAUUUCUUGAUUUUAUCUCAAGCCAGUACAGGAGGUGGCUAAAGCUUGCCUCCUGCCUUUGACUACAGAAACUACCUCUUCCUGAUAGGCUGUUCUGGAAUCCACUUCCAGGCAAACUGAACCCAGCAACCCGGUCAACACCAGGCCUAUAACCAUUGUAUAUAAUAGGCCAUGGAUACUAGAAGAUCCUGACUUCCGGGGAUGCUUGGAAAUGUAUUUUUAAAUGUUGUUUAAUUUGUUUUUUUCCUCCUUUUUUGGUGGAGAGGAGGCGCCAAGGAGUUUCAAACUGCUUGAGAACAUGGCGUUAUUUGUCAUACUUCCUCGUGUUCCCCUGAAAUAUCUUACACAAGACUGCAUAUUCUGUGGAGUCAAUAGAUAUUUGCUAAAAAUGAAUAACGUUAAAAGUUUAAGAAUUCAUGGAUGCUUACUGCCUAAGUCAUGACAUUGUGUCCAGAAUUGGUGGGUUCUUGGUCUCACUGACUUCAAGAAUGAGGCCGCGGACCCUCGCGAUGAGCGUUACAGCUCUUAAGGUGGCGCGUCUGGAGUUUGUUCCUUCUGAUGUUCGGAUGUGUUCAGAGUUUCUUCCUUCUGUUGGAUUCGUGGUCUCGCUAGCUCAGGAGUGAAGCUGCAGACCUUCGAGGUGAGUGUUACAGCUCUUAAGGCGGCUCGUCUGGAGUUGUUCGUUCCUCCCGGUGGGCUCCUGGUCCCGCUGACUUCAGGAGUGGAGCCGCAGAUCUUCAUGGUGAGUGUUAUAGCUCAUAAAGGCAGUGUGGACCCAAAGAGUGAGCAAUAGCAAGAUUUAUUGCAAAGAGCGAAAGAACAAAGCUUCCACAGCGUGGAAGGGGACCUGAGCGGGUUGCCACUGCUGGCUCAGGCAGCCUGCUUUUAUUCUCUUAUGUGGCCCCACCCACAUCCUGCUGAUUGGUAGAGCUGAGUGGUCUGUUUUGACAGGGCACUGAUUGGUGCUUUUACAAUCCCUGAGCUAGACACAAAGGUUUUUCAUGUCCCCACCAGAUUAGCUAGAUACAGAGCUAGACACAAAGGUUCUCCAAGGCCCCACCAGAGUAGCUAGAUACAGAGUGUUGAUUUGUCUAGCACCCUGAGCUAGACACAGGGUGCUGAUUGGUGUGUUUACAAACCUUGAGCUAGAGACAGAGUGCUGAUUGGUGUAUUUACAAUUCCUGAGCUAGACAUAAAGGUUCUCCAAGGCCCCACCAGAGUAGCUAGAUACAGAGUGCUGAUUGGUAUAUUUACAGUCCCUGAGCUAGAGACAUAAAGGUUCUCCACGUCCCCACCAGACUCAGGAGCCCAGCUGGCUUCACCCAGUGGAUCCCCCAACGGGGCUGCAGAUGGAGCUGCCUGCCAGUCCCGUGCCGUGUGCCUGCACUCCUCAGCCCUUGGGUGGUCGAUGGGACUGGGUGCCAUGGAGCAGAGGGUGGGAGGCUCAGGUAUGGCGGGCUGCAGGUCCCAAGCCCAGCCCCACGGGAAGGCAGCUAAGGCCCAGCGAGAAAUCAAGCUCAGCGCCAGUGGGCUGGCGCUGCUGGGGCACCCAGUACACCCUCCGCAGCCGCUGGCCUGGGUGCUAAGCCCCUCACUGCCCGGGCGGCAGGGCCGGCCGGCUGCUCCCAGUGCAGGGCCCGCCAAGCCCACGCCCACCCGGAACUCCAGCUGGCCCUCAAGCGCCGCCCGCAGCCGCCCGCAGCUCACGCCUCCGCCUCCACACCUCCCUGCAAGCUGAGGGAGCGGGCUCCGGUCUUGGCCAGCCCAGAAAAGGGCUCCCACAGUGCAGCGGUGGGCUGAAGGGCUCCUCAAGUGCCGCCAAAGUGGGAGCCCAGGCAGAGGAGGCACCCAGAGCGAGCGAAGGCUGUGAGGACUGCCAGCACGCCGUCAUCUCUCAACAUCAUAAAAAAAUGUUGGGGUAAAAAAUGUUUUACAUUUCAUUUCUGCUCAUUUUAAGAGCAUUAAACUCAUUGCAAAAUAGGGUUUAGGAUGCAGACUCUGGAGCCAGCCUGCUUCCGUUUCAGCCUCCACACUAACACUAACAAGCAGUGUACACUUGGAUUCCAGAGGGGUGACUACCAUAUUGAUGUCUGUAUCAAUGACUACCUGGAUGUUUUCUGCCCUCACUAUGAGGACUCCGUCCCAGAAGAUAAGACUGAGCGCUAUGUCCUCUACAUGGUGAACUUUGAUGGCUACAGUGCCUGCGACCACACUUCCAAAGGGUUCAAGAGAUGGGAAUGUAACCGGCCUCACUCUCCAAAUGGACCGCUGAAGUUCUCUGAAAAAUUCCAGCUCUUCACUCCCUUUUCUCUAGGAUUUGAAUUCAGGCCAGGCCGAGAAUAUUUCUACAUCUCCUCUGCAAUCCCAGAUAAUGGAAGAAGGUCCUGUCUAAAGCUCAAAGUCUUUGUGAGACCAACAAAUAGCUGUAUGAAAACUAUAGGUGUUCAUGAUCGUGUUUUCGAUGUUAACGACAAAGUAGAAAAUUCAUUAGAACCAGCAGAUGACACCGUACAUGAGUCAGCCGAGCCAUCCCGCGGCGAGAACGCGGCACAAACACCAAGGAUACCCAGCCGCCUUUUGGCAAUCCUACUGUUCCUCCUGGCGAUGCUUUUGACAUUAUAGCACAGUCUCCUCCCAUCACUUGUCACAGAAAACAUCAGGGUCUUGGAACACCAGAGAUCCACCUAACUGCUCAUCCUAAGAAGGGACUUGUUAUUGGGUUUUGGCAGAUGUCAGAUUUUUGUUUUCUUUCUUUCAGCCUGAAUUCUAAGCAACAACUUCAGGUUGGGGGCCUAAACUUGUUCCUGCCUCCCUCACCCCACCCCGCCCCACCCCCAGCCCUGGCCCUUGGCUUCUCUCACCCCUCCCAAAUUAAAUGGACUCCAGAUGAAAAUGCCAAAUUGUCAUAGUGACACCAGUGGUUCGUCAGCUCCUGUGCAUUCUCCUCUAAGAACUCACCUCCGUUAGCGCACUGUGUCAGCGGGCUAUGGACAAGGAAGAAUAGUGGCAGAUGCAGCCAGCGCUGGCUAGGGCUGGGAGGGUUUUGCUCUCCUAUGCAAUAUUUAUGCCUUCUCAUUCAGAACUGUAAGAUGAUCGCGCAGGGCAUCAUGUCACCAUGUCAGGUCCGGAGGGGAGGUAUUAAGAAUAGAUACGAUAUUACACCAUUUCCUAUAGGAGUAUGUAAAUGAACAGGCUUCUAAAAGGUUGAGACACUGGUUUUUUUUUUUAAUAUGACUGUCUUAAAGCAUUCUUGACAGCAAAACUUGUGCUCUCUAAAAGAAGCCUUUUUUUUUUUUCUAGGAGGCAGGUUGGGUGUGGAAUGCUAAUACAGAGCAGGUGUGAAAACAGAGAAAACUACAGGUUUGCUGGGGGUGUGUAUGUGUGAGUGCCUCUAAUUUUUUUGGUGACUGGGCAGUGCACACCAGAUAUUUUUUCUUUGAAUACAGAUCACCAUGGUGCUACAACUUUUUUUUUUUUUUUUUUUUUUUUUUUUUUUUUUUUUAAGAAACUCAAAGAGGCAUUUUUAUGAAUAAAGUGACCUUCCCCAAGGCUGACAAGCCAGGGUUGAUGAGUGCAUAGUGGAAUAGCUUUGGAUACUCCUCUGGGGGAUGACAUGUACCAAGGAGAGGACCGCAGUGGCCAGAGGAGACAUGAUUUGGCUUUGCUGGAGCGCCAGUGUGCUGUGGCCUUUCCCCGCCUCCCACCCUAGUACCCACGUUUUGCUCCACACUCCUUGACCGCAGGGGCUCGGACACAAACCCCUGUCACCAGGAGAGUCAGUCAGCACUACUUGGGAGGGCUAAAGGGAAAUUUGGAAAUAAAAUUCCAAAGUUUGGAGUAAAAAAAUUCAAGUGUUGAUUUUAUAUUCUUUCCCUUUCUGACACAGCCUAAAGCGUAGGGGGAACAUGUGUUUAUCUGUGGGAGAUAAACAAGAUGGAGUCCCAAAGACUUUAACAAAAUAUUUUUUUAAAAAUCCACUAGAAUAGAAAAUACAUUAUUUAGAUAUACUUUAUGCUGAGAGUGAGUAUAUAUGCUUGUCCUAUUUAAACUUGUGAGAAAAAGUGGUAUCCCUUGAUACAUUUAGAAAUAUGGGGGCUAUCUUGUUUCAUUGUGGGGGUGGGGCAGAAGGAGAAUAAAUGCAGGAUGACCCUGUUGAAGGAAUCUUAGCAUGGCCAACAGGGGACGUUUCCAGUCGAUUACCAGGAAAUGCAAGCCUUGGGGUUUCUACUGGUGGUGGGGCUGUCAUGAACUUUAAAAUCCAAAGCCUAGACAAGGAAAAGUGUUAGACCAAUUGAAAAGCAAUCCAGCCCUUUUUUUUUUUUUUUUUUUGGCUUUGCACGACAUGUCAACAGAAACCAUGCCUUUCAAUAUAAGAAAUAAAUGUGAUGAUCAUGUAAAAUGUGAAAAAUUGAAAGCAUUCCAGCAAAAUAAGAAUUUUUUAUAUAUUUGUUUUUUAAGAUGUAUAUGUUAAAAAAAGAGAAGGUCGCAUUAUGGACAGACUUCGUGAAUGGGAAUUUGCUUAGAAUUGUGAGUAGUUCUGAAUUAGAAAAGUAUGUGAAGGAAAGGCAGCUGUAAACGUAUUGUGCCCUGGAGAGUUGUACACAUGUUGAAAUGUAAUCUGGGCUUACCUGAUCCAUUUGGAGUGGAUGUCACUGCCGAGUCUGUUCUCACAUGGAACCAUGUGUGUGGGGUUGCCAGCCUCACAGAUACAAUCAAUCCUAUUCCCCUCUGACAUAAGGAACUCCUCUGGAGUGGCAGAGUCUUAUCACAGAAGGCAGCCACCAUUUCACCAAAACAAAAGUUCACGGCAUUCAAUUCCUUUUUCCUUUAGCUAUUUAUAUAUGCAGUACUCUCAGUCAUAUGCAGAAAUACUUUUUUUUUUUUAAUUAAUAGUUACAGGCUUGUUGGUCCAGUGGGAUUUGGGUAGGGGGAGAAAGAUACCUUCUAAAAUGGAUCAAUAGAACCAAAAUAAUACAGCAUGUUCUAUAACCACAAGGAAAUCAAAUGAUCCUGUCAUGAUUCCAGUUAGUCAUAACUAUGUUAGCAGUGCUAAAUGCAUUUUAGAAAUGGUGACUUCUGUGGUUUUCCUAGCAUUUGUCUCUAACAAAUGGUGAAAUAAUUACUCAUGGCCCUCUCUGCCAUUGUCUUUCAUUUUUUCACAGUGAAAUUAGACCCCUUUACUUCACCAUUCUGCCACUGCAAAUUAAGUAUAAAGAAAAUAGCAAGAGUGUCCACACCAGUAGACAGUAAGCUUCUCUACCUGUAAGUGAUGAAAUCAUAGCUAAUGCACUUGCCAUGGAGUUUUCAAGAUGAUUGGUGUCAGACAGUUUUCACUUUGUUUAAAAAGUGUUGGUGGCCUUUUGUGGUGGUGUUACAAUCCUCUGGGGGCUUAGGAGGAUGUUGAUGCAACUUUUAGAAGCUUUUAAUUUCAAAAACAACUCAAAAAUCUGAAGGACAGUCAUAGCUGCCACUCAGCCCCAGUUAGUCAAACCCCAGUGACCUUUGCCCCUGGUUGCCAAGGGCUUUGCAACAUCAAGCAGGGAAAUAAGGAUCUGUCUGUUUAGUGGAUACCGUGUAUCCUUUAAUAGACCAGGUAACAGUUCGUGUUAGUUUAGACUAUUGUUUUGUACUGUACUUUCUUGGGUGGCAGAGGAAAGAAAAGUAAAACAUUAAAAAAAAAAAAAAAACUGCGUUCUUUAAAUUCUGUAUUAUUAGCAACCUCUGUUGUACAUAGUGUUUGAUAAUAAAGUAUUAAUUUGAUUCUUAUGUCUUUUGUAAGUGAGAACAAUAGACUUUCAGGAUACAAAACAUGCAUUGAGGCUUUGAAACAUCCAAUGUGUACCAUGGCUGAAAAAAAGAGUCACAAGUGGCUGAGACACUGCUCCAUACAGGACUCAUGUGUGGUCAUUGCCCACCCAAUCUUAUGACUCCAUCAUCUUGGGACCUGGAACAACAUGACUUUUUUGAUCGAUAUUUUGUCCUCGGUGUUUUCAAGGUCUGAUGUUGGAGCCCUGUGGCCCACCCUCCCUUCUCCACCAGCAUGUUGGUUUGAAAAGGAUAGGGAAUUUAGAAACAGUUCUGUACUUUGGUUUGGUUUGGUUUUCUGUUUGUGAUUGUUUUCAUGGACUGUUUUAUUUUUUCCCAGGAAGAGUCUUUAUCAAUAUCAUGUGCAGCUCACUCAUGGAAAUGGUUGCAAACCAAUCAGUGUAGGAAGCUUAAAUGGGGCUGUUUCCCUCUCUGUGUCGUUGUGAAAGGAAGAGUCACACAGUACCUGUGGAUUUUCAGGGACUCUGUUUUUCUCCGGUGCCUUAGCAACGGCAGCAGCCAUUUGUAUUAUUUUCAAAUAAUUAGAAAAACAGUUUUCAACUCCUCCUUUCCAUUCAUUGCUCUCAGAGUUGUGGUCACUGACUUUUCUUUUGAAAACCGCCUCCACCAACACCCCCGUUUGCCUACACCACCCCCCUUUUACUUAGUAUGUUUAUUUUUUGUGUGUCUCUUGCCUUCCUCCCACGUUUUAUUUCCCCUCAGAGCUGUGAAUGGGCAGGUCUGUCUCUGGUUUGGCAUCACUGAGUUUUUCCCAUGCAUUGGCCCCAGGGCUGCUAGGAUGUGAGACAAAUCUCCCUACAAUGGGCUUGCUCCCAUUGUCUGUACAGUUUAAUAGAUGCUGGCAUGUCGGAGGUUACCCAUGAGUCAAAAUCCGCUCUCCAUGCUUACUCUUGACACCCCAUUGAAGCCACUCAUUGUGUGUGCGUCUGGGUGUGAAGUCCAGCUCCGUGUGGUCCUGUGCUUGUACUGCCCUGCUUUGCAGUUCCUUUGCACUUACUCAUCGAGUGCUGUUUUGAAAUGCUGACAUUAUAUAAACGUAAAAGAAAAUGUAAAAAAAAAAAACCCACACACAAACAAACCCAUACGAUCUGUAUUUGUAUAUACACGUGUCCGUACAAGUAUAACUAAAUAAAAAUUAAAGAUUUUCAUCAUUUUAA